AGAAGCGGCAGCGCUCGCCAUUGCCGCUGGUGGCAGGAGGCUGCGAGGAGCCGGCGCGGUCGCAGUCUCCACGGCGCAGGCCCACGGUAGCGCAGCCGCUCUGAGUAGAACUUCAUGGAGGAACACGGAGUGACCCAAACCGAACAUAUGGCUACCAUAGAAGCACAUGCAGUGGCCCAGCAAGUGCAGCAGGUCCAUGUGGCUACUUACACCGAGCAUAGUAUGCUGAGUGCUGAUGAAGACUCGCCUUCUUCUCCCGAGGACACCUCUUACGAUGACUCAGAUAUACUCAACUCCACAGCAGCUGAUGAGGUGACAGCUCAUCUGGCAGCUGCAGGUCCUGUGGGAAUGGCCGCUGCUGCUGCUGUGGCAACAGGAAAGAAACGGAAACGGCCUCAUGUAUUUGAGUCUAAUCCAUCUAUCCGGAAGAGGCAACAAACACGUUUGCUUCGGAAACUUCGAGCCACGUUAGAUGAAUAUACUACUCGUGUGGGACAGCAAGCUAUUGUCCUCUGUAUCUCACCCUCCAAACCUAACCCUGUCUUUAAAGUGUUUGGUGCAGCACCUUUGGAGAAUGUGGUGCGUAAGUACAAGAGCAUGAUCCUGGAAGACCUGGAGUCUGCUCUGGCAGAACACGCCCCUGCGCCACAGGAGGUUAACUCAGAACUGCCGCCUCUCACCAUCGACGGAAUUCCAGUCUCUGUGGACAAAAUGACCCAGGCCCAGCUUCGGGCAUUUAUCCCAGAGAUGCUCAAGUACUCUACAGGUCGGGGAAAACCAGGCUGGGGGAAAGAAAGCUGCAAGCCCAUCUGGUGGCCUGAAGAUAUCCCCUGGGCAAAUGUCCGGAGUGAUGUCCGCACAGAAGAGCAAAAGCAGAGGGUUUCAUGGACCCAGGCACUACGGACCAUAGUUAAAAACUGUUAUAAACAGCAUGGGCGGGAAGACCUUUUGUAUGCCUUUGAAGAUCAGCAAACGCAAACACAGGCCACAGCCACACAUAGUAUAGCUCAUCUUGUACCAUCACAGACUGUAGUCCAGACUUUUAGUAACCCUGAUGGCACUGUCUCACUUAUCCAGGUUGGUACGGGGGCAACAGUAGCCACAUUGGCUGAUGCUUCAGAAUUGCCAACCACGGUCACCGUUGCCCAAGUGAAUUAUUCUGCCGUGGCUGAUGGAGAGGUGGAACAAAAUUGGGCCACGUUACAGGGAGGUGAGAUGACCAUCCAGACGACGCAAGCAUCAGAGGCCACCCAGGCGGUGGCAUCGUUGGCAGAGGCCGCAGUGGCAGCUUCUCAGGAGAUGCAGCAGGGAGCUACAGUCACUAUGGCGCUUAACAGCGAAGCUGCCGCCCAUGCUGUCGCCACCCUGGCUGAGGCCACCUUACAAGGUGGGGGACAGAUCGUCUUGUCUGGGGAAACCGCAGCAGCCGUCGGAGCACUUACUGGAGUCCAAGAUGCUAAUGGCCUCUUUAUGGCAGAUCGUGCAGGUCGCAAGUGGAUCCUGACUGACAAAGCCACAGGCCUGGUCCAGAUCCCUGUGAGCAUGUACCAGACUGUGGUGACCAGCCUCGCCCAGGGCAACGGACCAGUGCAGGUGGCCAUGGCCCCUGUGACCACCAGGAUAUCAGACAGCGCAGUCACCAUGGACGGCCAAGCUGUGGAGGUGGUGACAUUGGAACAGUGACAUACAGCCAUAUUAUGGCAUCGUUUUCUAGUCUACUUCAAAAUUUUUUACACGUUUGCAGAGGUGCAAUCAAAUGGAAUUAAGUCUCUCGACUUUGGAAGGAAAGUUUUGUUAACCUUUUUUUUUUUAAAAGGAAGAAAGCGGAUUUUGGAAUUGCAUUUUUUAAAGCACCACUCUUGAUUUUCUGGGAUUGGUGAAGAAACUGCAUUGUCAAUUUCACUGUCCCAAAAAAGCCAAAUUGUGGCAGGACUUCUUUCUGCGGAAAUGUGUGUGUAUACUUAUGUGUGUGUAUGUGUGAGUGUGAAUAUAUGUAUAUGUGUACAUAUGGACAUACACAUUUACAUAUAUAUAAAGUAUAUAUAUACAUAUAUAUAUAUAUAUAUGUAUGAAACCCGCAUGGAAUUAUCUGUAUGAAAUCAAGGUGCGCUGUGGAAACAAUAAUUCACCCAGUUUAGUGGGUGGUAGGGUACGUGGCCAGACACAGUCACCCAGUUUUUGUUCAUACCAGGGUCAUGCGUUGAGCUACUGACAAACUCAGGCGGAGGUGACCAUGCCCUUCACCAAAGCUGCCUCCCAGUGGCCACACAGAACUCUCCCUGCUGGACUCACCUGAGGAAAGAGGCUCCAGCAUGGGGUGGGUCAGAGAUGUGCUUGCAAGGUCCAGGGACUGCGUGGUCUGCCAGCUGAGAUGCUCCUCGGGCUGGCCCAGGUGCUGACCUUGCCACAGGCAGAUGAAUGUCUUGAAAGCUCCCGGGCCUCAGCCUCCCAUCUCCUCUCCUUCCCAGGAAUCCUUGAUCUCAUGACUAUUAAAAUGUUGCUCUGGUUUUAAGGUCAGUCCUGAAUUGCUCGUAUAUAUGAACUGAAGGUAACCGAAGUAUUAGGGGUUUGAGGAGUGCGUGCGUGUAAGUGUGCUUGUGUGUGUGCGUGCAUGGUGGGGGAGAGGAUGGGAAGGGGGCGGGGGCAGUGGAAGGGAAAGGAAGGAAAGAAAAAUCGUCCUAGACCAGGAUACACCCGUGGGAGCAAUUUUCUCUACUGUCUGUAGCUUCACAGAGGAGGCGCUGGAAUGAACAAGAAGAGACAUCUGGUCUGUGGCCACAGCACCCUGAACGCCCCUGAUCUUGUGUGAUCUUGGAAGCUAAGCUUGGUUGGGCCCGGUCAGUACGCGGAAGGGAAGAAGGGACACCUGGCCAUAGAAAACAGCUGAGGGUGUUUGCUGUGUUCCUGGAUCAGGCCCUGCUUCAGAAGGGACUCCUGGAGGCCCAUGUUCCUUGAUGCAACCUCGUGGCCCAGGCCGGGAGCAGCUUGCCUCCUCAGAGGUGUUGACUAUCUGGGUGUUCUUGGUAACCGUUAACUCUGUCUUUCUCAGCUGCAAGCCCUGAGUCUCCAGUAGCUGAAUUCACCUGACUUUUCAACAGGCCAAAUCUCUGAACCUUGAGUACAGGGACAGCUCCUCCUCCCUCCUCCCAGCUCUCCCCAUGUGUGUGAUGGUGUAUUUAAUGUGUUUUUUUAAUGCGACAUUAAAAGAUUCUCCACGUCUUGCUCAACCUUUGAGAGAAGUUUCAGAUUCUUGUAUUUGCUUGUUUUAUAUAAAACUAUCUAAUGUUCUUUAUAUGUUCUUUUCUGUACGUAAUGGGGGGAGGGGAGGGAAAUUUACAUAUAAAUAGUCCUAGUUCUACAAUUUGUUAUUUUUUUAAUUAUUAUUUUUUAUCGUCAUUGUGAAGUUGUCCAGGGACUUUAAAGUCCAUGUUCCUUUGUGGUGAAAUAACCUCCAAAUAGUUUGAGAAGUUGCCAAGACGAAGAAAAAAGCAAAACCCCAGUAGCAGAGCAUGGAUUCUGUGUUGUUUCCCAUUCUGUCUUUGACUGCCUCAUUCAAUAAAUAGUUAAAAAUGUGGCAA